AGCCGCCAUUUUCUCGCCGCUUGUGUGGCUCGCUGGCUGCGUGGCUCGGUUCUUGUGAGCGAAGCUUUGUCCGGUUCGGCAAUGGACGGAAUCGUCACUGAGGUUGCAGUUGGCGUGAAGAAUAUCUGAUCUGGACUUCUGUGGAUUUAUGGAAGAGCUGGCUUUAUUUCUCUAUCCUGUGGGAGGGGCAAACUUUGAUUUUGUAUGUGGAGUAACUUGACCUUCAGUUUUUUUGGUCUGAGAACAAAGGCCAAAAAAUAUGUAACAGUUAAUAACAGAGGAUCUGACGAACUACUCUCAGGCAGUGUUCUCAGUAGUCCGAACUCUAAUAUGAGCAGCAUGGUAGUUACAGCCAAUGGUAAUGAUAGUAAAAAAUUUAAAGGAGAAGAUAAAAUGGAUGGUGCUCCUUCUCGUGUACUUCAUAUUCGAAAAUUACCUGGGGAAGUAACAGAAACUGAAGUUAUUGCUUUAGGCUUACCUUUUGGUAAGGUGACCAACAUCCUUAUGCUGAAAGGAAAAAAUCAGGCAUUUUUGGAACUAGCAACCGAGGAAGCAGCUAUUACUAUGGUUAAUUACUAUUCUGCUGUGACACCUCAUCUUCGUAACCAACCAAUAUAUAUCCAGUACUCGAAUCACAAAGAACUAAAGACAGAUAAUACAUUAAACCAACGUGCUCAGGCAGUUCUUCAAGCUGUGACAGCUGUCCAGACAGCAAAUACUCCUCUUAGUGGCACCACAGUUAGCGAGAGUGCAGUGACUCCAGCCCAGAGUCCAGUACUUAGAAUAAUUAUUGACAACAUGUACUACCCUGUAACACUUGAUGUUCUUCACCAAAUAUUUUCUAAGUUUGGUGCUGUAUUGAAGAUAAUCACAUUUACAAAAAAUAACCAGUUUCAAGCUUUGCUCCAGUAUGGUGAUCCAGUAAAUGCUCAACAAGCAAAACUAGCCCUAGAUGGUCAGAAUAUUUAUAAUGCCUGCUGUACCCUAAGGAUUGAUUUUUCCAAACUUGUGAAUUUGAAUGUAAAAUACAACAAUGAUAAAAGUAGGGAUUAUACUCGACCUGAUCUUCCAUCUGGGGAUGGACAACCUGCAUUGGACCCAGCUAUUGCUGCAGCAUUUGCCAAGGAGACAUCCCUCUUAGGGCUUCCUGUUGCAGCUGUUCCAGGAGCUCUGAGUCCUUUGGCCAUUCCAAAUGCUGCUGCAGCAGCUGCUGCAGCUGCUGCUGGCCGAGUGGGUAUGCCUGGAGUCUCAGCUGGUGGCAAUACAGUCCUGUUGGUUAGCAAUUUAAAUGAAGAGAUGGUUACGCCCCAAAGUCUGUUUACCCUCUUCGGUGUUUAUGGAGAUGUGCAGCGUGUGAAGAUUUUAUACAAUAAGAAAGACAGCGCUCUAAUACAGAUGGCUGAUGGAAACCAAUCACAACUUGCCAUGAAUCAUCUUAAUGGACAGAAAAUGUAUGGAAAAAUUAUUCGUGUUACUCUGUCUAAACAUCAGACUGUACAGCUACCUCGAGAGGGACUUGAUGAUCAAGGGCUAACAAAAGAUUUUGGUAAUUCCCCAUUGCAUCGUUUUAAGAAACCUGGAUCCAAAAAUUUUCAAAACAUUUUUCCUCCUUCUGCCACCCUUCACCUAUCUAAUAUCCCUCCAUCAGUAGCAGAAGAGGAUCUACGAACACUGUUCGCUAACACUGGGGGCACUGUGAAAGCAUUUAAGUUUUUUCAAAGAGAUCACAAAAUGGCUCUUCUUCAGAUGGCAACAGUGGAAGAAGCUAUUCAGGCCUUGAUUGAUCUUCAUAAUUAUAACCUUGGAGAAAACCAUCAUCUGAGAGUGUCUUUCUCCAAGUCAACAAUUUAAAAAUGGGAAGAUGAAGAUUGGGGGUGAAUCACAUUGUUCAAUGUCAUCACCUAUUUGACUGUUCAGAAAAGUGGGGACCAGAGUUUGAUUUUUUUUGUUUUUGUUUUUUUGGGGUUUCUUUUUUUUUUCCAUGCUGUUAUCAUUCCUUGGUUAUAAAAUGAAAUGGCAUAUGUAAAGGCAGAGUUGUUAACUGCUAUAUUUCAUCUGUUCUAUAGGGAAGCCAUUUUGUCUGUUUAAAAUUUCAGUUUAAUUUUGCUUUUUUUUUUUUUUUUUUUUUCCUUUCAACUUAGUUGACAUACGUGCCUUAAAAAGGAAAACUAGUGUUGCUAUUGUGCAUUUACUAGAAAAAAGGAAUUGGUUGUUUAGGGCACACUGUUAUAUGGGAAUUAAAAUAUGUUUAGGCAGGGGUGUGUAAAAAGGUUAAGUUUUUGUUUCUCCUGCUUGGAACUUAUUUUGAAUUACUGGCUUGUCACCUUUUUUUCUAUUUAAUCAAAUAAGAUACAUGAUAUUGAAAGAAUAAAGCAGCAUUUUUAGUUUUUACUACCUUAGGCUUUAUUGCUUUGAAAACAACAUUGGCCUUUUGUAUCUCACAAUUCUGGUCUAGAUUCAGUUAUGAAUGUAGGCAUUAGUUAAAAUUAACAAGAUGCAGAGUAUUAAUUUCUUAAGACAACAAAGUGAUUUCUGUAAGUUUGAGCCCUAUGUGGAAAGCAUUGUGGAAUCUUAACCUUUUCGUACACACUCUUGUGGGACGUAUCAUAUAAAUGUCAGCACUAAGUAAUGUCUUGUUUGUGGCUGAAUAUUUUUCGUAGAUGUUUUUGAAGUUGACAUGACUUACGUGCAUUUAAAUAUAUAUUGCCAUCCUUAGUUUGUAAUUAAGAUUUGGAAUAUGGUUGUGGAUUUCUGAGCAUGUGCAGACUGGUCUAGCUAGUUCAGGAACUGGUGCAUGUAUUUUUCAAAGAUAAAGAAAGUGUACUGCGAAAAUAUGCAGGAAGAUUAAUUUUGUGGCAGUUUUCUAAAACUGACAACCAGGUGGGACCAAAGUUUAUGUGCCUUUAGUCUUAAUUUACCUUGCAUUGUAAUAUUCAGUUUUAAUAAAUCUUCAAAAUAUUUUGUAUUUAGGAAUAGAUCUGACUUUAAUAAAAACAUGGCUCAGAAUCUACAGGUCAAAUUAAUUUGAACAGUUCUUGUCAAUCCGAAUUGUUGAUUCUGUUUAAAUGACCAAUACUUUUUGAAAUUGAUGUACUUAGUUUCAAGAUUCAUAGAUUCUGUUAUCUAUGUAGACAGAAUGGUCAUGUAUAUUUUCUAUUAGUUGAGUUUUUACAUCUUUAGAAAUGUAAAAUUCAGUAUAGUUUGAAAGCGGCACAAUUAAAAAUUAAUUUUCUAACAAAGUUGGGAGGUUUGAUGGUUGUUUAAUUUCAUUUUGUGUGUACUCUGCUUACCCCUGUAGCAUGCUCAAUAAACACUUCUGUAGCUCUAUAUUCACCUUUUCUGUCUUUCUCUGCUGCCUUUUCUCUCUCCUCUUCUUUGUUUUCACUCCACUGUGCUUCUGAAUUCAUGUUUAUUCUCUGCCAGGGUGGGAAAGGAGUAAUAAUAUUACAAUUCUAUGGCUUUAUACCAUAAAUAAAUCUAGAUGCUGUGAAAAUAUACCAGCUGGUUUUUUUUAAUUUAAAAGAUGGUAACUGCUUUUCAGGAGGACACAUAUUAAACAUUUCCCACCCUGUUAUAAUCUACUGCUUUAAAGACAUAACUUUUAUUGUAGCUUGUUAAUUCUAUCUCUUUUGUUCUUGUUGUUUUUUUUUUUUUUCCAGUAGAUUUAUGCACUAAUAGAUCUUUUGGAUUUGCCAUGCUCUCUUGCUGCAGUUUCAUCUUUCAUCUUUUGUGUCUGCUAAAGAUUUCUUACUAAUCUUAGACUACCUUGUGAGUUAACAAAAAGAACUUGAUAUUACUGGGAAGAAAGAGCAGCAUAUCUGCAUAUCAGCAUAUCUGCUUUUGCCUUGGGUGGGAAGAAUGAUAUACAUUCAAGUAUUUAAAAACUUAGAGUAAUUUGCAUUUAACAACUGAGGAUGUUACUACUGUAACUUGUUAAGCAGUUACAAUUAGGGUGCUAUUUAUAUUCAAAAUAUUUCGGUCAGUUUUUCUAAACAGAUAUAUUGGUAUCAAAUAACUUUGGAGUUACACAUGUUUCUUAGGUUUGUUCUGUUAUAAAAUAUCCCACACUUAUGCAAAACUUACACAUAGGAUAAUAAAAAGUAAAUGAAGGAACAUAAAAUAUGUUUUACUAUACUUAAUGUAGUAAUUCAGUUACCUCCAAGAAAGAAGAAUAUAAUAAGUAAAAUAAUUUUGUUUACACUAGUGUCACUGUUGUCAUCUGAAGAAGAACCAUUAGAGUCAACAGUCUGGGAUGAUUUGGAAGCUAGGUGAUCUGUGUUUUUUUCUUAAAAUAACAUCGUAGCACAGAGGAACUCUACCAGCAUCAGAUAAGUCUAAAGUCUAAAAAACCAAUACCAGGGUUAGUGAAUAGUAAUUGAACAAAGCUUCUCAAGGUGAAGUUUUUCUCAGUAAUUAGUGGUGGCUAUAAUAUUUGAAAGUAGGUUCUGUCACCUUUUCAGGUGCUCAUUGUGGGUGGGAUUGCCUUGGGAAGGAGAAACUAAGUCCUGAGCUGUGUGUGUGGACUUAGUUUGUGCCAGUUGCUAAGCUGGUGGGAGUUCCCAGUCUCCCUAGUGGGAGAUAACCAGAAACCAGCUCUUCCUGCCUAAGGACUACAGCAGAUUCUAUACUGUCUUACAGUAUGCCCUAAUACGGCCUUCCUUCCAAAGCACCAAGUCACUAAAGGGGGAUUUUGACAUUCUAGAAUAUUUUUAAUUCAGUACAUCAAAUUAACCCAGGCCUUGGCAUAUAGUGAAUUGCUUAUUAAAAGUUAGGUAAAAAUAAAAACAGCUUUGUCGUAUAUUAGUACUCUAUGACUCUUAGAGUGAACAAGCUAACAAGUAUUCUUAGGACUUAGCUGCUUUGUUAAUAGAGGUCUUAACUUGAAUAUUUAGAAAUAAUCAGAAAAAUUAUUUUUUGGUAUUGAAGAUGUAUUUUGGAAAUGGGUUUUAAAGUACCUACUUAAGGAAGAGAUAUCUACAGUUUAUAUUUAACGUUAGCAUUUGAAAGCAAUGAAGAAAAUUUUUCCUUAACCAGGAAGUGUAAUGAAUCAUUAUAUUAGAGAUUAAAUUAACACUUUGGAAGCAUUUUAGCUCCUAGAGUUAAGGUUAGUAUAGUGAAAUUAUGGUGAUUAGCUUAAUUCAUUCAUGUACAUCUAUUUGUAUCACCAUAUAAUUACUAGGGAAAGGACAAAUCACUUUUCAAAGCCUCAAUGUUAUUUGUAAAAUGGAGGCAAUAAGUUCUGCUCUGCUCCCCUCACAGGAUUAUUACAGAGGCUCAAAUAGGAUAAGUGAAGGAAUGCUAUGCAAUUAGUUAACUAAUGCCAGUUCCCAGACUGCCAGAUUUGCCCACAGUAAACUUCAUUAUCCACAAUACAUGUUAUCCUAAUAUGUCUUUUUGCUACAAAGAAAUACUAAUGUUUUAAAAUUAUUUACUAGUUUCAUAAAGCAGAAAGAUGUAAAAUGCAGUUAUAGAGAGCAUCCCAAGCCAGAUGAAAAGAAACCAUGGAUUUAGCUUUAUAUUUUCUGUUUGAACUUGAUAGCCCAAUCAUAAAAUGCACAUAUUUAAUUAUAGACUGCACUUAAGAUUUCAUAUGUAUAAAAAAGUUGCUGUGAAACAGGUAAUUUUAACACUCAGGAAUUUCAAGGCUAAGGAAGAAAGACAUACUCUCAUGAGCAGCUCUGAACUUCAAACAGGAUUUUCUGGCUGCCUUAAUAUAUUAAAAUGGAGCCUAAAUCUGAAAACGUUUUUUUCAUUCAGAAGAAAGUACAGAAUUCAGUGAAAUUGAGUAUACUAGGAAAUCUGAUGGCAAGAAUUCAGCAGAAAGUCUUAAUUUUAAACCGUAAUAUUCAUUGAUUAUGCAAAACCUUAGUUUUAUAGUUAUUCUUUGUUAUUUUGAAUAGCUUCCCUUUAAAUUUUCUAGUUUCAGAUUUUGCAAAUAAAAGUGUACAUGUUAAAGUUAUAGAGUAUUAGAUUAUUCACAUUAAGAACUGUUCAAAUACGCGGAAAAAUAAAACCGUAAUGAACACCUAUGCACUUCACUCAACUAUAUCACUACCUAACAUAUUCCAUAUUUUAAACGUAAUUAUAUAUUAGUUGAAAGAAAACGUUACAGAAUGAACUGAAAUCCCAUAUGAACCUCUUUCUGAUCUUAGUUCAAACCUUAUUCUUUCCCAAGAGGUAAUUGUUACCUUCAGUUUAGUAUUUUAUUAUUCAGUGGUUGCUUUUCAAGAGGAAUUUGUCCUAUAUUCUGUAGGCUAAAUUUCUUGUUUUGCCUAGUUAUAAAAAUGGCAAAUAAUAUGAUAUUGGGUGUUUAAAUAGUACAAUAUUGUUCAAAACACACUUUAUAAUUUUUAACAGACUGUUUGGACAUUGAUAAUUCCCCUAUCAAAUCUCAUGACAUUUAACCAAUUUUUAACAAGGAUUUUAAAUUGUGUUUAAGAAAUAAGUCAUUUGGGCCUCAGGUUUCUCUUAAGGAUGUAAACAAGGAGCUAUAUCAUUGGUAUUUUAGACGCUGAAUUAUGUGUAAGGUCCUUAAAUACAAACAUACCCUUUGUAGCUUCACAGAGCCACCCGUUUUGCACUUCUCUCGCUUUUCUUCCUCCCUCUUUGGCUCCCAUUUCAAUGGACAGAAAGACUAUGUGGCAUCUCUAUUUUCAUUCACUUGGUUUAUUGUCUUGGUAUGUUGUAUAGGUUUUUGAAUCAGAAAAUUUUAACAUUUUUAGAUAUUUCAAACAUACAAAAAAUAGAAGAAUAUUUAACAAACCCUUGUCAGCUUCAGUUAGCAACUUAGAUCUUCCUCGUUUCCUCCACCCAAUUCUCAUCUCCUUUAUUAAUGCAGAUCCCAGAUAUAUUUUAUCAAGAAAUUUUGUAGCAUAUAUUUGUGUUGUUUUAUUCGUGGUCAUAGUUGCUUUCUCUAAUAUCUAGACUAGCCUAGCUGGUCAAUACUACUUUUCUUCAAAUCCUAGAACCUCCCUAUUAAAAAUAUAGUCACCAGACCAGUGGCAAAUUAGUAUCACCUAGGAGUUUAUUAGAAACUCAGUCUAUGAGCCUACUGAAUCUACAUUUUGACAAGAUUGGCAGGUGAUGCAUUUGGACAUAAGUUGGAGAAGCACUCAAUGCAUUUUUUCAGUUCUAUAAAAAUCAGCUUCAAAGUUUUUUCCUGAGUGUGGAAAUUAUUUCAUUAGUAAUUUUAAGUUAUGCAGAUAUAGUUAAUACCAAGAAAUAAUUGAACUGAAAAGGAACCCGGAUAUCUAGUUUUAACCAGCUGUUUUAAAGAUAAACAGUUCUAGAGAUCAAAUGAAUAGUUUAGCAACAUAUUUAUUGUAACUUACCUGUAGUUAGAAUCCAAGUCCCUGGCUUUCCAAUCCAGUCUUCAAUGUAUAAUACUGAUCAAAAGAAAUACAGGCCUGCUAUUAUUCAUAAAUUUAAACUAUUAUGUACAAGUUGAUAGCUUAUAAUAGAAAUCAGUAUGAUUAGUGUUAAAAGUCAAAUUUAGUCUGACAGGGAAGGAAUGUCCAUGUGAACUGAUUUUUUUUAAUAGAAUGCAAAUUAAUACUCAAUUCCUGAUUUGUUUAUUACAUUUUGUGGUUUAAUGAAAUGAUACUCAGGUCAUUUUCAUAAAUAGCUUUUCUAUUAAUGCUUCCUCAGUCACAUUCUCUAUUCCUAUUGCAUAGCACAGUCUAACAGUUGAAAUGCCUAAGCCUUACUGAAUGAUGACUGAUAUUCUCUGUGAGAGUUAGAGCUGUACUAUAAAUAUACAUUACCUGUGCAAAGUAUGCCUUCAGGGGCUAUUCCCCAUAACCUUAGCAAAAUUUUAAAAUAUUCUUAUGGCUAGCAAUCUUAUCUAUUGUCAUGUCUUACUAUUUCCUGCUUACCACCCCCAUUUCUCUCUCAACCUUGUUGCUGCAUUAGCUGUCCAUCACUUAACACUGUUUAUUUCUCUGUUUUUCUUCCAUCAUUCUCUUCUUUGCAACUAAAUGAUUUAGACUUUUUAUAACCAUAAUCAACCAGUUAGAUUCUUUUUAUUUGUGGUUAUUGAGUUGAUAAAUGAUAGUGCAUUUUAUGUAAUAUUCAGGUGUUAUGCUAUUUUUAUCUGGUUCACUUUAAAACCUCCCUCCCCCCACUCCCUUUUUUUGUGGGUUUUUUUUUUAUUAUUAUUAUUUUCCAGUUUUGUGUUGUUUUGCUUUUUAACUUCUGAGAUUGCAGUGGUUCCAGAUGGUUGAAAUCACUAGUAGUGAUUUACAUGAAGCAUUCAUGUAUUUAUUACUGGUAUAUUCAACUAUGGUGGAGGGAAAUUGGUCGAAGAAUUACGGUUAAAGAGCUCCUUUAAAAAGGAGAUUUGUAGAAUUCUAAAAUGUGAUUCUGAUUCAUAUAGUCAUGAUUCUUAGAAAUUAGCUACAGGAAGAGAUAGAAACAUUGCUAUAGUUGUCUUUGCCCUAAGUUUGGAGUUUUAUAGUGUAAUAUAUAUAUAAUAGCUCUAAUUAUAAAUACACUUUUACUCUGGAAAAAGCAUAGACAUUGACAUAAGAGACAUUUAAAAACCAUUAUUUUCUCAUCUGUAAAAUGGAGAGAAUUACUUCAUAUGUUCACUUAUAAGGAUUAUGUGAAAUACUGUUCCAUUCCAUUAGUAGUUUUUCUUUUCCUCUAAUUGGGGGUGGGGGCAGUUUUUGGCAUUCUAUUUAUGGAAGGUGUUUUUUUCCCUAAGAUCAUUUUGAUGUCUCAGAAGACAUUUGCUAUGUACGUUGGACAUUUGCCAUGUACAUUGUAGAGAAUACAAAGAUAAACAGAACCACAGUACAGCUGGUUCUAUUAGACAUUGAAAAUGCAUAUUCUAGCAUAUUUAAUAUAUUAGGGAACAAUUUAAGCAUAAUGUGAAUUUCAUGUUUACUGAAGAUUUCAUCCUGAGAAACAAAUGAAAGCAGAAAAUUACAACCAACUGAACCAGCUGUGUAAGAAAUAUAUAUAUGGUGUGCACACAUGUACAUACCUCAGACAUCUAUUAGCAUUCUCAGUUUUCCACAAGUUAAAAGCCACGCUCAUCCAUAUCUGGUGCUAAUAACUUCCUAUCCAAUUUCAGAUAGCUGUUUUCAACACAUCUGACACCUUCUUUUUUUCAAGCAAACUUCAGGUCUUUUUCAAGAUAAAGUCAUUUAUAGUAGUGUCUAUAUAUUUCUUAACCAUUUAACAUGUAAACUGUGCUGCCUUUUAAGAAAUUAAUUCUAUCCUUUUUAGUGUCAGAGUUGAAGAUUUUGAGUGUUGUGCCCUAACCUUAUCAUUUUCCUCAUAAGUCCUGUGGUUUUUAUUGUAUGAUUUUGCAUAGUGUGGCAAUUCUUGGAAAUGCUUAUGUUGUGUUAUAGUAUAACUGACUUACUACUUUCAAAUAGCUUCUAGUCUGAUUCAUGUUAUGACAGUAUACAGUAUAGCAAAAUAAGGACAUCAGGGAACAGGAGGCUGAGCAUAUCACCAUUUACCAAUGGUAGCUUGAGCAAGGCACUUCAUUUAUCGAAGUCCAUUUUCUCAUCUGUACAAUGGAGGUGAUGAUAGUACAUGUCUUUUCUGUCUUGUGUUAUUUGUAGUUUCAAGUAAGAUAUGAAAUAUGCUGUAGAAAUACAGGGUUGGGAAUAUCUAGUGGUACAAAAAUCAACUUUUGGCCCAAUUUUAAGGUGAGAUAAUUAUGAGACAUUUUUCGACCUCAAAGUCUUUGUUCUUUUCUCUCUACACCAUUGUGAAUAACACAGUGUAUAUAUGAGAUUAAUUUAUUACCUCGACUUUCCAUUUUUGUUUUGUAAAGUAGUUUAAUUUUUUAUAUCUAUUUAUAAAGUUAACUGCAGGAGUGUACCUGCAGUUAACUUUAUACAGUUAAGAAGAGGUUGGUUUCAGUUUUAAAGAUUGUAUGUCAGUGUAAAACAUCCAUUAUUAUGCUUUCAAGUAAAAUAGCUCCUAAAAAUAUGGAUUACUAUCAACUUUCAAGGAAAAUAGCUCCUAAAAAUAUGGAUUACUACCAACUUUCAAGGAAAAUAGCUCCUAGAAAUAUGGAUUACUAGCCACAUAAAUUGCUAACAUUUGCUUUUAUUAUUAUUAUUAUUAUUAUUUUAGACACAGUCUUGCUCUGUCACCCAGGCUGGAGUGCGGUGGUAUUAUCUCGGCUCACUGCAACCUCCACCUCUCGGGUUCAAGCAAUUCUCCUGCCUCAGCCUUCCGAGUAGCUGGAAUUACAGGCACCCACCACCACACCCAGCUAAUUUUUGUAUUUUUAGUAGAGACAGGGUUUUACCAUGUGACCAGGCUGGUUUCGAACUCCUGACCUCAAAUGAUCCACCUGCCUCAGCCUCCCAAACUGCUGGGAUUACAGGUGUGAGCCACCGCUCCCAGCCUAUUUGCUAAUAUUUAACCUCUUGAGAGUCUUUAAUUCUUUUUUUCAACAAGUGUUCAUUACCUGCUAUGUGCCAGCUUAGAUGCUUUGGAUGAAAUACAGGUUGGUGCGAAAGUAAUUGCGAUUUUUGCCGUUAAAAUUAGAAAAACCACAAUUACUUUUGCACCAACCUAAAUAACUAAAACACAAUUUCUUCCUAUCAUGGGGCUUUCAGUUCAGUAUGAGAUAAGUAAAGAAUUAUAUGGGUUGAUAAAUUUUCUGGAGGAACUAUUGGGUGUUAUUACAGUGUGCUCAAUCUUUAGCAGUUAGGAAAGGAUUCUUGAAGGUAGUUGUAUUACCUGGGUUGGAGGUAAGUGUUGGGGACACAAGUGUUAGAAACAGAACAGUUUGUUUAAAAGUUGGGGACAAAAAAGGACCAGAAUCAAGAUUACGGCACCCUGGAGAAAGUUAAGCAUGGCUCGGUCAUAAAUUAGGAGACAAGGAACAAAUAGAGAAAUACGUUUGGAUAGAAUAGUCAGAUUAUAGGCUGUGCUAAGUUGUUUGGGCUCCACUAGGGUUUCUAAAUGCAGUUAUUGGUAAACUGGACUUAGGAGAAGGGACAGGGUUGACAUGACAAAUCUAGUGAAUUUAUGUUCAUUAAAAUAUCCCUUUUGAAUUGAUUUAGUUUUUGUAUGUUUCUUUUUUAUAAUUCCAAAAAAUCAUACAAAUAAGUUAAACUUAUCCAUCUAAAAGCUGCACACAAAACUUGAUGUUAGAUUCUUUUAAAAUUACAAAAUUAAGACUUCCAAAAGAAUCUUGUUGAAUAAGAGUAAAAGAAAGACCCUUACUCAGUAAAGCUGCGUAAUACUUUGGCAGUUUGAACCCAUGGCCAUGCCUCUCUGUGUGAUAAGGAUUUGGCAAAACCAUGGAAGAAACAUGCAUGUUUUUGAAUUGUCUUUCCAUGGUAACUUAAAACAUUUUUUCAUGAAACAUGGAUAUAUAUCCUUAGAAAACUGCAAAACAUAAAGCUUGUAAGUUAUAAGACAAGAUUUAUCUCUUUUUUUUUUUUUUCUGAGAGAGAGUCUUGCUCUGUUGCCCAGGCCGGAGUGCAACAGUGUGAUCUCUGCUCACUGCACCCUCCGCCUCCCGGGUUCAAGCAAUUCUCCUGCCUCAGCCUCCUGAGUAGCUGGGACUACAGGCGUGUGCCGCCAAGCCCAGCUAAUUUUUUUGUAUCUUUAGUAGAGACGGUUUCACCAUGUUGGCCAGGCUGGUCUCGAACUCCUGACCUCAAGUGAUCUACCUGCCUCAGCCUUCUAAAGUGUUGGGAUUACAGGCAUGAGCCAUGGCACCCGGCCAAGAUGAAAUGUCAAGGCCAUUUUAGCCACUAUGCUUUUAAGACUACUUAAAGCUGUGCUUUCAGGUCUCCCCAGGAAUACUUGUUCACUCUAUACUAUUGCUGCUGCUGUUCUGGCUUGAGAAUUUUGAGAAUCACUAAGAUACAAUUUUAAGUUUUGACAUGUAAAUUAUUUGGUUGAGUAGAAAGAAUUAAUGUAGAUAAGCAAAAACCCCUUUAUAAAAAAUGCUUACCCUUUAAAAAAUGUUGAAUCCUCACAGUAUGAUUAAAUACUACUUGUAAAAGUGUCUGUUAACCAUAAUGUAUUUUUUAGAUAAUUUGAGUAGAAUUAUACGUGCAAUAUAUUCUUGAGUUUGUGACCAACAAAGAAACAGAUUAAUGAUUGAAAAUUCACCAUACAUUACUACCUAUGUCUCUCCACCUGCUAUCUACUUCCAAUUUUUUAUAUAUAUAAAAGUCAUUAAAGUCAUUUGUAAUUGA